GCAUUCCUGACCGGCACCUGGCGAGGCUCAUGCGUCCCGUGAGGGCGGUUCCUCGAGCCUGGGGGCGCUCAGAUUGCUUUGGAGACGCUGAGAGAACCUUUGCGAGAGCGCCGGUUGACGUGCGGAGUGCGGGGCUCCGGGGGACUGAGCAGCACGAGACCCCAUCCUCCCCUCCGGGUUUUCACACUGGGCGAAGGGAGGACUCCUGAGCUCUGCCUCUUCCAGUAACAUUGAGGAUUACUGUGUUUUGUGAGAGCUCGCUAGGCGCCCUAAGCAACAGAGUUCUGAGAAAUCGAGAAACAUGAUAAGGAAUUGGCUGACUAUUUUUAUCCUUUUUCCCCUGAAGCUCGUAGAGAAAUGUGAGUCAAGCGUCAGCCUCACUGUUCCUCCUGUCGUAAAGCUGGAGAACGGCAGCUCGACCAACGUCAGCCUCACCCUGCGGCCACCAUUAAAUGCAACCCUGGUGAUCACUUUUGAAAUCACAUUUCGUUCCAAAAAUAUUACUAUCCUUGAGCUCCCCGAUGAAGUUGUGGUGCCUCCUGGAGUGACAAACUCCUCUUUUCAAGUGACAUCUCAAAAUGUUGGACAACUUACUGUUUAUCUACAUGGAAAUCACUCCAAUCAGACCGGCCCGAGGAUACGCUUUCUUGUGAUCCGCAGCAGCGCCAUUAGCAUCAUAAACCAGGUGAUUGGCUGGAUCUACUUUGUGGCCUGGUCCAUCUCCUUCUACCCUCAGGUGAUCAUGAAUUGGAGGCGGAAAAGUGUCAUUGGUCUGAGCUUCGACUUCGUGGCUCUGAACCUGACGGGCUUCGUGGCCUACAGUGUAUUCAACAUCGGCCUCCUCUGGGUGCCCUACAUCAAGGAGCAGUUUCUCCUCAAAUACCCCAACGGAGUGAACCCCGUGAACAGCAACGACGUCUUCUUCAGCCUGCACGCGGUUGUCCUCACGCUGAUCAUCAUCGUGCAGUGCUGCCUGUAUGAGCGCGGUGGCCAGCGCGUGUCCUGGCCUGCCAUCGGCUUCCUGGUGCUCGCGUGGCUCUUCGCAUUUGUCACCAUGAUCGUGGCUGCAGUGGGAGUGACCACGUGGCUGCAGUUUCUCUUCUGCUUCUCCUACAUCAAGCUCGCAGUCACGCUGGUCAAGUAUUUUCCACAGGCCUACAUGAACUUUUACUACAAAAGCACUGAGGGCUGGAGCAUUGGCAACGUGCUCCUGGACUUCACCGGGGGCAGCUUCAGCCUCCUGCAGAUGUUCCUCCAGUCCUACAACAACGACCAGUGGACGCUGAUCUUCGGAGACCCAACCAAGUUUGGACUCGGGGUCUUCUCCAUCGUCUUCGACGUCGUCUUCUUCAUCCAGCACUUCUGUUUGUACAGAAAGAGACCGGGGUAUGACCAGCUGAACUAGCACCCAGGGACCCAGUGUACCCAGCCUCUGGCCUCGUGCCCUGCUGGGGAAGGCCUCACCCAGCGAAGGCCGGAGAAGCGGUUGGGCCCUGGCACACAGGGCUGGCUCAGUGUGCGGACAGAGGAGACCACUCUGCUCCUGGGGCCAGAGGCCAUUCAAUAGCCUGCCUUCGUCCGGGCCCCUCCUGGGCCUCCCCGGCCAGGCACGUGGCACCGUCGCCUUGACACCGCCAUCUCUUUUCUUUAAGGCUUCAGGCAGCGCGCACAGGCUCUGGCAGCCGUCUCAGGCAGGACUGGGCACCAAGCUUGCAGCCGAAGGCCUUGCCCCAAACUACCAGCGUUUCUGCAAGCAGCUUGAAGGGCUGACCUUGCAGCCGGGUGAGCCAAGGGCACUUUGCUGCCACCGCUGCAUUCCCAGAGAUCAAGCAGCCCGGUGCCGUGGCCAGUGAACUCAGAGGUGCUGGUGGACGGGCUAGGACUUUGGGGUUAGGCCAUGGGGCUCUUUCUCUGAAGGCCACUUUCCUGACGUACUCUCUGUACAUAACUCAGCGUCCGUGACUGCAGUAACAGCCAGCCCUACCCAGAGUAUUUCUGAGCCAUGAGGGGCCCACCAGAUUGGUUCUGAAUUGGAUUCAUGCCCAGCGCAUUAGCAUAGUAACUCCUUUCAGAUUUUUUGGAGGGACGUUUGGAAGUGGCUUACUCUCUUCUGCCCUCUCUCCUACCUCCACCUUCUCAGAUUAGCCCCAUCUGAGCACAUCCAGCUGCUCCUUACCCAGCAUCUGGAGUACAGGACAUAGCUCUCUCCUGCUACCAGUCUGUGCCUUAGAGGUCUGUUAGGCCUGCCAAACGGCGACCAGCUCCCCUGGAGCGAGGGCAGGCCCCUUCCCUCUCUUUCCCCAGACACCUACUUGAGACUCACCAAUUUCUGGCCUGUUCAGGAGCCUCAGAUAAGUAUUUGUACUUGAGACCACCUCACACAAUCUGUAUGGGCCCAACCCUGAUCUCAAACCUCCUUCCCUCUGCCCAAAGCUGUCCUUCCUAUGGCAGGAGGGGUGGGGGUCCCAGGACGUGCCUCAUACAUGACUUGAGCUUGUCAGUCCACUGAGUUUCCUUCUACGAGAUCAACGCGAGGGGCCUGUAUCUUGAAUUAAAACCUACUCGCUUCCUUUCUGCACUCUGUGUGCUCGAUACAGAAGGCAGGUGUGCUGGCCUUCAGAGCCAGGUGCCCUGCUCCCCUCGUGUAAGGAAGCGCAUAAGGUUGUGAAGGUCACUGACCCGAGAGCGCUGCGUGCUGACCCCACACUUCACUGGGGAGCCCUCUUGGGUAGCGCGAGACGCCUACCCGCCCAGGGCCAGGUCAGUCUCCCAGGCUCCGUGUCUUCACGGUUACCAGGGCACGCCACUCAAUCUGGAUGUGAGCCGGGGUGGAUGAGGUUCUGAAGGGCACACCAGCACUGGGAGCGGGGGCAGUGGGGGUCUUAUUCUCCAGACGCUUCCUCUAUCUAGUUGUAACAAACGUCAAAGAAUGUCAGGUCUUGUUUCUGCAGAGCAGACUUUGGCCUGACGGGGUCCACAGACCUGUUUCACUUGCAACACCCAGUAAAUGUGUUACUGGGUGCCCUACUUUAAAAAUCAGAGAUUUCAAAUGAUUGACUUUUCCGGCUGAGUGCGGUGGCUCACGCCUGUAAUCCCAGCACUUUGGGAGGCCAAGGCAGAUGGAUCACCUGACAUCAGGAGUUCGAGACCAGCCUAGCCAACAUUGCAAAACCCCAUCUCUACUAAAGAUACAAAAAUUAGCUGGGCAUGGUGGCGGGCACCUGUAAUCCCAGCUACUUGGUUGGCUGAGGCAGGAGAAUUACUUGAACCCAGGAGGCGGAGGUUGCAGUGAGCGAAGAUCACGCCAUUGCACUCCAGCCUGGGCAACAAGAACGAAACUCCAUCUCAAAAAAAAAAAAAAAUUAUUGACUUUUCUUUAAAAUCUGAUUUGGCAGUGCUAGGUAGGUCCAGGAGUGCUAACACCUUCCCAGAGGUGGUACGCAGGUAGUCAGGUGCUCUCUGACUCACCCCCAUCUGGCCAGAUCACGGCCCCCAGCAACACGUGGGGUUGUGUCCCUCGCUGGGAUACACGGAGUGCCCUUAUAGGCAGGGAGUCUUAUAGGCAGGGGUCUCUCCCAGGCACCUCUGGGUGUCCCUACGGCCCCUCCCAGGUGGGAGCUGAGGCUAGGUUGCAAAAAGGAGGUUGGGAGCAAGUAGGGGCUUCACAGUAACACCCAAGAAAGCACACGCACCCCAGGGUCCCACCCCAGUGCUCCCAGACACUCCCACAGAUGUGGUUCUGGUCAGGCGCAGUGCAGCUGCUGCGGCUCCACCAGCCCCGGGCUUUCAGGCAGGUGGGCCUGGGAGUAGUUGAGCUUUGUCCCAGAACAGUGGGGGAUGGGGCCAUCAUUAAAACCACAGCUCUGGCCCCAAUAUCCCACCGCCACCCCCACCCCGAUAUCCCAGCCCAUGCCUCAGCAAAGCCCCCUGUGAAUUCCAGCAUUUUUAUUGAGCGCACCACAUCGGGGAGGGGCGGCAGUGGUUUCCACGGUAACCAAAGUAAGGCUUGUGCACUUGCUGAGCUUCCAGAUGCGAAUUAGUAAAAGCUAAAUUCAAAAGUAGAAUGGGCAUCUCCAAAGAGUACGAUAAAAACAUUUUGUAUCAAACUUGUGAUUAAAAAAAUACAAAAGUUAAACCCA